AGCAAGCUGUCCUGUGAGCCGCCAGCAUGGAUGACAUCUACAAGGCUGCGGUAGAGCAGCUGACAGAAGAGCAGAAAAAUGAGUUCAAGGCAGCCUUCGACAUCUUCGUGCUGGGCGCUGAGGAUGGCUGCAUCAGCACCAAGGAGCUGGGCAAGGUGAUGAGGAUGCUGGGCCAGAACCCCACCCCUGAGGAGCUGCAGGAGAUGAUCGAUGAGGUGGACGAGGACGGCAGCGGCACGGUGGACUUUGAUGAGUUCCUGGUCAUGAUGGUUCGGUGCAUGAAGGACGACAGCAAAGGGAAAUCUGAGGAGGAGCUGUCUGACCUCUUCCGCAUGUUUGACAAAAAUGCUGAUGGCUACAUCGACCUGGAUGAGCUGAAGAUAAUGCUGCAGGCUACAGGCGAGACCAUCACGGAGGACGACAUCGAGGAGCUCAUGAAGGACGGAGACAAGAACAACGACGGCCGCAUCGACUAUGAUGAGUUCCUGGAGUUCAUGAAGGGUGUGGAGUAGAUGCUGACCUUCACCCAGAGCUGCCUAUGCCCAGCCUCCAACUCCAGCUGAGUCCUGGGGUUGGGGAGGGGGUCGGGGUCCCAGGACCUGAGCCUGGCCAUGUCCUCAACCCCAAAUCCCCCGACUCCCUCCCCAGAUCUGUCCUGGGGGAUGCAAAUAAAGCCUGCUCUCCCAA